CUGCGCCAUGUGGGCCUGAAGCGCGUGUCUGCUGUCUGUGCCAGUGCUCCUGCCGGGUCCCCUCAGGUGUGUCGUUUCCGUCGCGCUUCCGCCCUCUCGGCCAUGGGGGUCCCCAAGAGGAAGGCCUCGGGCGGCCAGGACGGCGCGGCUUCCUCCGCGGGUGCAGCCAAGCGCGCCCGCAAAGAAGAGCUCACGGGCGUGCGGUUCAAGGCUCAGCUGAAGGACCCGCAGGGCCCCGGGCCAGGCUUGGAAGCGUUUGUGUCUGCUGCCAAGAAGCUACCACGAGAAGAUGUGUAUGAUGUUGUGGAAGGGUAUAUAAAGAUUUCUGUUGAGUGUGUCGAAAUUUUCCAGCUCCUAAGUGGAGAGAAACGACCUGAAAGUGAAACGAUGUUAAUAUUUCAAGUUUUCGAGGCCAUAUUAUUGCGGACAGCAAGUGAUCUUUCACAUUUCCAUGUUGUGGGAACCAACAUUGUGAAAAAGCUGAUGAACAACCACAUGAAGCUCAUCUGUGAGUCCCUGUAUGCCUCAGGUUACAGGUUGGCUCGCGCCUGCCUGAGCCUGAUGACCGCCAUGGUGACCCAGGGUCCGGAAGCUGCCAGGGACGUCUGCAGCCAUUUUGAUUUGAAUAAAAAGACCCUGUACACCCUGGUGACCAAGAGGGAUUCAAAGGGAGUGUACGACGUUCGGCAGGCCUACGUUCAGUUUGCUCUCUCCUUUUUAAUUGCGGGUGAUGACAGCACUAUAGUGCAGGUGUUGGAAGUGAAAGAAUUUAUUCCUUGCAUUUUUAGCUCAGGGAUAAAGGAAGAUAGGAUCUCUACCAUCAAUAUUUUAUUAUCCACACUGAAAACAAAGGUAGUUCACAAUAAAAAUAUCACAAAAACCCAGAAGGUGCGUUUCUUUACGGGGCAGUUAUUGAACCACAUAGCAUCGCUGUACAACUGGAAUGGGAUUACCGAUGUGAACCCAGAAAAUGUCAAGGUUUCUGCCGAAGAAGCAGGGAAAACCAUGGUGCGGGAGCUUGUUCAUAACUUCCUGAUGGAUCUUUGCUGUUCACUCAAGCAUGGAAUUAAUUUUUACGAUGCAUCUUUGGGUACCUUUGGCAGAGGCGGAAACCUGACACUCUUGCACUUCUUGCUGGGUUUGAAAACUGCAGCUGAUGAUGAUCUGGUGGCUGACCUUGUGGUAAACAUCCUCAAAGUGUGCCCGGACUUACUGAACAAAUACUUCAAGGAAGUAACGUUUUCCUUUAUCCCACGAGCGAAGUCUACUUGGUUAAAUAAUAUCAAACUACUAAACAAGAUCUAUGAGGCUCAGCCGGAGAUUUCCCGGGCAUUUCAGACCAGAGAGUUUAUACCCUUGCCUCGGCUCCUGGCAAUGGUGAUGGUGACCACCGUGCCCCUGGUGUGCAAUAAGAGCAUGUUCACCCAAGCAUUAAACUUGGACAGCACCUCAGUGAGGCACACAGCCUUAUCCCUUAUUUCUGUCAUUUUGAAGAGGGCAUUAAAAACUGUUGACCACUGCCUGAAUAAAGAGGUGUGGCAGGAAUCAGGCGUGUACACAGCUGUGAUGAUGGAAGAAUUCGUGCAGCUCUUCAGAGAAGCCCUGAGCAAGAUUUUGCCAGACCUGAACACUGUCGUGUGGGUCUGGCAGUCACUUAAAAAGCAAGAGACCAAACAGGAUGACAAGAAAGGGCAGAAAAGGAGCGAUGGGCCCCCGGCUGCCUGCGAUGCUCACCAGUGCGAUGAUGCAGAAACCAUUCUUUUGAAAGCUGUUUUGCUCCAGGUCAUAUGCCUCUACCAGAAGGUGGUCCCCCACGUGGUCAUGCAGUACAACUUUGACUUCAGCAAGCUCCUGAAAGGUGUCAUCUCUGAGCAGGGCCUUCGAGAGGAGGUGCCUCCCAUUCUGCAGCACCACAUGCUGAAGGUGGCCCUGGAGCUGCCGGCCAGCAAGUUUCUGUGGUUAAAGGCACAGGAAGGCCCAGAUGCAGAAAUUAUUGGAGGUGAACGAUCAGUAUUUUACUUACUAAUGAAAAUGUUUGUGACCAGUAGCCAUUUACAACUGAAGUCAUUGACCAAACUUCUGAUCAUGAAGAUUCUGCGGGACACGGGGGUGUUUGAGCACACCUGGAAGGAGCUGGAGCUCUGGCUGGAGCAUUUAGAGAACACCAUGGAAGAGGACAAAGAGACUGUGAUUCAGUUUCUGGAACGCAUUUUAUUGACAUUGGUGGCGAAUCCCUAUUCAUACACAGACAAAGCAUCUGACUUUGUCCAAGAAGCAAGCAUGCUGCAGGCCACUAUGACGAAGCAAGAAGCCGAUGACAUGAGCAUUCCCAUCUCCCACAUUGACGAUGUUCUCGACAUGGUGGAUGUCCUGGUGGAGGGCAGUGAAGGCUUGGAUGAGGAAAUAGGGUUCACGUUGAGUGAAGACAUGAUCCUGCUCACGUUCCCAUUCAGUGCGGUAGUCCCUGCGGCCCUGGAAGCCAGGAAUAAGUUGCUCCUUGGGACAGGCAAUGAAGCAGCGGAAAACGUUGUGACAUAUCUGACGGCAGUGCUGACUGACCUCCUCCACACCCAGAGGGACCCCCUGGCUCUGUGUCUCCUGCUCCAGGCAUAUGAUAAGCUUGAGCCUCCAUGCCUGGUGCCUUGCUGCCAGCAGCUCUCACGGUUUAACAGAUACUACAGCCUCUGGAUCCCGGAGCAAGCCCGAGAGGCCUGGCUGCUGCAGGCACAGGGCAGCCCCUCGCCCCCUGCCCUUCCCUUGGCCUCGUCCUUCACAGCCCUGCUGCAGGCAGCCUACGAGAGCCAAGCGCUUCGGGACGAGCACAUCCAGGUGCAGCUGCAGGCCACCAUGCCACACCUGUCCAUGCAGCAGGUCCUGCUCGCGGCCAAGCAGGUGUUGCUCUACCUGCGGAGCACUGUGGAGAACUUCGGCCAGCUGGGCAGAAGUGUGGGCCCGCCCCUCCUGCAGCUCUUCCUGGAUCUCCUCAGGCGCCUGGUUGUCCACUGUGAGCAGCUGGAUGCCCAGAACCAGCAGAGAUGCGAGGCCGCCCGGGCCGAAGCCGACCUCUUCCUGGACAUGGAGUCCGUGGCCUCGCUGGAGUUGGCCAAUGAUCAGACGCUGGAGGAGGUGCUUGUGGCCAUCCUCAGGCACCCCACCCUGGAGGGCUGGUUCCUGGCCCUGGAGCAGCAGGCCCUCCCGCCGCACACGCUCAGCCCUGUCCUCGUGAAGCUCCUGGCCACCCACUUUAGUGCAGGGGUCCUUCAGCUGCUGGCAGCAAGUGCCCCGAUCCUCCAGAACAUUGGGCAGCUGGGCCUUCUGGCCAGGUACUCAGAGGCCAUCACCCAGAGUGUGCUGAAGGAACUUCAGAACAGGAGGGCGGGCCCGGCCACAUCACCACCAAAGACCCCGCCGCAGCUGGAGGCCCUGCAGGAGCUGCAUCCAUACAUGGAGGGUGCCCAGCUCCGUGAGGUCACCCUGGCCUUGCUGAGCCUGCCUGAGACACACCUGGUGACCCAGCAACCCACGAAAUCCCCCGGGAAGGAAAGACACCUGAAUGCUCUUGGAAAGACCCUGGUGCAGCUGCUGACCUGCAGCCCCCAGGAUCAGCUGCAGAGUGGUGAGCUCCUGUGGUCCUCCGAGUAUGUGAGAGGCCUGGGGGCUCUGCUGCCCACGCUAGCAGUGGACGAGCUGGACACAGUGCUCCUCCACACUCUGCAGAGAGACCCUGUGCUGGCCCCCGCAGUCGGGGCUGAUCUGCUUGACUACUGCCUGGCCCGGCGCACACAGGCGGCCCUCAGCAUCGCUGCCCUGCUCCUCCAGGAGAGCUGCACCCACUUGCUGUGGUUCGAGCAGUGGUGCCUGCAGGCUGGCCCAGGGCUCGGCCUCCAGGGGGACCUGGACGACUUCCUUCCCCUCAUCCAUGUGUACCUCCAGUGCAGGACACGGAGCCACUUCACACGCCCAGCAGGAGUGUCUUCCGCUGUCAUUCCUGUCUUGAGGAAGACCCUGUGGAGGCAGCUACAGAGCAGGCUUCUUAGCACUGACAGUCCCCCAGCAUCUGGGCUGUACCAGGAGAUCCUGGCACAGCUGGUCCCGUUUGCACGAGCCAAGGAUCUCAGUGUACUCAUGGACCGCCUGCCCAGCUUGCUUCACACCCCAAGCAGUCACAAGAGGUGGAUCGUGGCCGACUCCAUUUCAGCAGCUCUGGAAGGGUCAGCAGAAGAGCUGUGUGCCUGGAGAAGGACCCUUUUGGAGUCCUGUGUGAAGUGGCUGAUCGUGUCUUUCAGUGGUGGACAGCAAGAUGAUGAUAAUACUCAGAAUCAGGAGAAGGAAAUGCUGCUUAGAUUAAAUGCGUUGUUGCAUGCACUUAAUGAAGUUGAUCCUGGUGACUGGCAGAAAUUCGUGAAGAAGGGACUCAAAUUUCGGUACCAGGACCACACAUUUUUAAAGAUGCUCCUCACCGCCGUACAGCUCCUGUACAGCCCAGAAAGCUCCGUGCGCACGAAGCUCAUCCAGCUCCCGGUGGUCUACGUGAUGCUCAUGCAGCACUCGCUGUUUCUGCCGACUCUACUGACGUCUGACGGAGAGGAGAGCCCGGACAGCCAAGUAAAAGAAGCGCUGGUGGACCUGAUGCUGACGGUGGUGGAGAUGUGCCCCUCUGUCUGUGAGAGCAGCCACUUUGCAGUGCUUCUCGGGGCCUAUGGCGCCACUCUCAGCGUCCUAGAUCAGAAGAUUUUACUUCUGCUUCGAGCGUAUGAGCAGAACAAGCUCAGCCUCAUCAACUUCAGGGUGCUGCUGUGGGGCCCAGCGGCCGUGGAGCAUCACAAGACGUGCCGGAGCCUGGGCAGGUCACUGUGGCAGCAGCCGAGUGUCGGGGACAUCCUUCGCCUGCUGGACCGGGACCGGAUGAUGCAGACCAUCCUGCACUUCCCCCAGAACCGGAGGCUGCUGCCCCCCGAGGACACACAGGAGCUGAUAUUCAAAGACAAAAGCAGGGUGGAUCUUGAUGGCCUCUAUGACCCCUGCUUUCUCCUUCAGCUCUUCAGUGAGCUGACCAGGCCAGAGUUUGUGGUGGAUUGUCGAAAAUUUUUGGAUUCAAAUGCUCUGGGCCUAACUGUCACAGCCCUCAGCAGCUAUGACCCCCAGAUGCGAGCCAUAGCCUACCAUGUCCUGGCGGCCUACUACUCGCACUUGGAGGGCGCACGGUUCCAAGAGCAGUCCCAGCUACUUUACCUGUUGGAUGUAGUCCGGAAUGGGAUUCGAACUCAGGACAUGAGACUUACUUUUACCUUGGCUCUCUUCAUUGCCAAAGCAGCCCUGCAGAUUUUGAAACCAGAGGAGCACAUGUACCUGAAGGUCAGCAACUUCCUGCUGUCGCAUGAGUACUUGAACAUGGACAAAGUGCCAGGCUUCUACCAGUUCUUCUACAGCUCCGACUUUGAGCAAAAAACAGAGCAGAAGUGGGUGUUUGGCGUUCUGCGGCAGGGGAUCCGUGACAAGCAGUGCUACGAACUGUGUGCCCGGCGUGGCAUCUUCCACAUCAUCCUGUCCUUCUUCCACAGCCCGCUGUGUGACGAGGCAGCACAGAAUUGGAUUCUGGAAAUUCUACAGAAUGCUGCCCAGGUUGCCAGAUCUGCGUAUGAAAUCAUACGAGACUAUAGCCUUUUAACAUGGAUUUUACACAUCCUUGAAAGCAAGUUUCUGGAGACUCCGCUGCUGUCUAAUGUGAUCUCCUUGCUACACACACUGUGGGUGACCAACCUGGGGGACAAGGCAGUGGAGUGGGAGAGCCAGCGCCUUUGCCAGCCUAGCUCCCAGGAGCCUGCCAAGCGGCUUGCCCUGCACCUGGUCAAUGAGUUCCUUUAUGUUCUCAUCGUGCUCAUGAAGCACCUGAGGCCCACCUUGGCCCCCGUCCAGCUGACCAACUUCUUCGGGACACUUGACUCCGUGCUGAGGUACCGGGCCACUGUCAUACAGGCCUUUAGGGACAUGAACAGAUUCACCGUAAAUGAGACAGUGCUUUCCACCAAGGACGUCCUUGUCCUCUUGCACAAGUGGAGCCUCAUUGAAAGAGACCUCAAGCUCCAGGAAGACCUGAGAGCAGCCAUUGAGAAGGCCCAAGCCCGGGAGCUCAUGAAAAUGCUCAAGGAUAAGAACAAGCCUGUCAUGCCAGCCCGAGCCAAAGGCCCACGGGGCCGAAAGAGGAGGCCUGGGGAGGCAGAGGAGAUGGCUGACCCUGAGCUGAUGGCAUCUACCUUGGAGACAUGCAAGGGCCUCCUGAGGUCCAUCUUGACUUACUGGAGACCAGUGAUCCCUGGUCCUGACCCCACUCAGGAGCCUGUGGACUCAGCCAGCCCCGAGAGCGAUGCGCCAGGCCCCGUAUAUGCUGCCGCUUCCCUGGCAGUCAGUUGGGUGCUGCGGUCGGUGGCCGAGCACCCGCUCAGCAGGGCAGAGGCUGCAGGACUCAUUGGCUGGCUUAAGAGCCAUAUUUUGCCACACCCUGUGGUCGUGGCUGACCUCCUUAAGGACAGUGCCGUGAGGAGCAGCAUAUUCAGGCUGUAUAGCCGGCUCUGUGGGGCUGAGGGGCUGGCAGGGCCUGUGCAGGAGGUGGCCUGCCUGUUCAAUACGGUCAUGCUGCAGCUGGUGGCUGCCCAGGGCCGGGCAGGGAGCCCCUUCCACCCGGCCAUGGAAGCCCUCUCCCUGUCUUCUCUGAGUGAGAAGGAUGAAGCCACACAAGCCUCCGCAGCAUUCCUAGUGUCUCUCUACAUAAAGGACAUCUGGCUGGGGGCUCAGCGGCCGGACACCCUCUUAACCCACGUCCGGAUGGUGUGUGAGGCCGCAGAUGAUGCCCCGAGCAGUGAAGAGGAGGCCAUCGUGGUGCUCUGCAAGGACGCCGCCAGCGCAGCCUCAGAUGCUUGACUCCUGCCGGCCAGCACCUUGCACCCUGAUGACCAGAGCCUCGAGCACAGCACCAGCUUCUAGAAGUUUGGUUGAGUCAAGGGUUUCCAGAGAAGGCAUGGGAAACAACAGGUUCAGUACAUUGGCUCAGUUCUUUGACAAGAAAAGUUGAGAGGACUUUAUUGAACUGCCCAGUAAAUGAUAAACUCGGGCCUGUAGGUGCCCAGCAUCAGAGUUGCAAGGAAUGUGGGGACUUCUAGGCCAUGAGGCCCAUCCAGUGCCUCGUCAGGCCGCCCCUUCCUCUCUAGGGGCUUGGAGCUCAUCACAGGAAAUAGCUCGAGUUUGAGGCAGCACUUCUGAAUGCAGAAGAGAUUCAUCUGUGUUAAAGCUGAAAUGUCAAAAGGUAUCAGAUUUUUUUUAUGAAAACGAAGAGAGAUGUUUAAAGUUUAUUUUUCAGCAGGUGAGGUGGCUCACGCCUAUAAUCCCAGCACUUUGGGAGGCCAAGGCGGGUGAAUCACCUGAGGUCAGGAGUUCGAAACCAGCCUUCCCAACAUGGUGAAACCCCAUCUCUACUAAAAAUACAAAAAUUAGCCAGGCAUGGUAGCGCACACCUGUAAUUCCAGCUACUCGGGAGGCUAAGGCAGGGGAAUCGCUUGAACCUGGGAGGUGGAGGCUACAGUGAGCUGAGAUCGUGCCAUUGCGCUCCAGCCUAGGUGACAGAGCAAGACUCCAUCUCAAAAAAAUAAAAAAAUAAAGUUUGUUUUUCUAUAAAAAGUCAUAACAAAGUAUUAGUAUGACUUUUUGAAUAAGUUAAUUUCUGCCAGUGUUUAAUUAUUUUAUUAAAGAAAAGGAUGUUACACUGAAUCCUUAAAGAAUAAAAGUGAUUUGACCUCUGCUUUGAGAAGACAGCCUGUAAUUUUUAAAGCUAUACUUCAAAGAGGGGAUUUUGAAUUUUAUAAAUGCUUGUUAAUGUCUAUUUUUGUAAGGUUUUUGUGUUUUCCUUUCAUUGUUGUCAAGAGGCUAUUUUUGCUCCACAUAGGCCUGCAUUUAUUUUAAAGGUCAGAAUUUUACUCUUAAUGGUCAUAUAUUAGUUGGGGUUGUAGCUGACAAAAGUCAUGAAAUUUCGUGGUUUUCACAGUUAAAAUUUCCGUCUGUUCCUUUAAAACUCUCCUGCAUGCCUGGGGCUCUUGGGAUCUGCUCUGUGGCCUAGGAUGUGGCUGUUUUAUCUGCCGUAUAAUGUACAUCGUGCUGACAAUGCCUUGGUUUUGUCUGAAACAUUUACACUUCUAUUUUCCACCAGUGUUCUUUAGAAUUGUUUCUGUUUUAGGUGACUUAAAGUUUUAACUAAAGCAUGAGUAACGUUUGUUGGCAUACAGUCCCUUCACCACAAAUAAUUGUCUUGCACUGUCUACAAAGCAAGGAUCAGUUACCUCACUUGUCCCCUUCCCUACCCAAAUAAACCUUACAACGCUAUUCUUUGAGACUAUCCUGAACUUGAAAUCCCACGUUUAGAUCCAAGCUGGACUCAGGCAAGCGCUGCUCCAACAAAGCGUUCUCUUCCUGGUUCCCCUUAAUCUUUAUCCACCUCUCCAAGGCCUAUCUUUGGGGAUUCCUUUGGUUAUAGGCACCUCUGCUUGUUUAUGCAGGGGGCAUUGGCCGGAAGGACAUUGGUCUGGGGAAUAUCCCUGAACCCCAUGCCUCUGGGGGCACAGGGAGGGGCAGCGAGCAGGUGGGGUGGAUUUCCACGGCUUCAUCCCUGGCUCCAGGCCUAAGCUGCCUCCCAGGUUCUUAGGGCCCAGCAAGUCAAUACAUACUACGUCAGGUGGCGACAAAUGCUCCAAAGCCGAGUUCCAGCUCAGUCAAGUGAGGACACAUUUUCAGCACCUCACCUUCUUUUCUGCAUCUCUGGAGCUCAUCAGUCUUGCUUUUCUUUGUUCUCCCUUUUAAAUCCACUGCCCUGACCUUGUUCGUGUAUUUUCCAGUCACUUAGUGUGGAGGAAGGGAAUCUCAUCCCAUGGAGAAUAGAUCGAACAUGGUCUUCACCUGACUUAAAAUAUAAAAUGCUAAAUUAGAAAUAUCUUAAGUGGGGCGGGGGGCACAGUUAUUUUAAAAAUAAAACCUAUCAACUCCCUCCUUGCCUGAAAGCUGUAGGGGACAUAUGGGUCUUCUGAGAUUUGCUGUGUGAUGCUGUCUCCUCUCCAGGGACAAGGCUGCUGGGCACUAGAGGACUAGAUCUUUCAAGGGUCCCAGAUCCACUGUCACAUAAAGUCACAUCCAGAAGACCUUUCCUGCCAGCUUCCAGGGCUCUUUGUGUUCUGUGACAGCAUUUGGGCAUAGAUCCUGCUUACCCGGCCUGGCUGCUGACAGGCGUUGGCUGCCUGCCCUCCAGGGGAGACACUUUCUUGGGCUCUGUCUUUGAAAGGCUGUGGGGAGGUUGAAGGUGCAACUCAGGUCCCCAGACUGCAGUGAGCUGACCUGGCAGGGCAGAUGCCAUCACAUCUGGGGGAGCCGGCGGGUGUUAGUGGAGCUUGGAUGGGAACUUACCCAGCAUCCUAACAAAGGUACAGAAGGACCAGGUGAACUCAGGGCUGAUAACGCAUUACACAGUAAUGGUAAAGUGGCAUAGUAAAGAUUAGUAAGCAAACAGCUUUUCCUCUUGAUUUGCAUAUAUUUUAUUUUCCUACUCUUCCCUGAGCAAAUAUAAGCAGUAAGCAAGCAGGCUAGGUGUGCUCAAUAAACUCAGCAACACCUGGGAUGACCUCUGCACUCGAGGGGCCACUGCAAUCUUUGUCAAAGGCAUAGGAUGCUCCUGCUCUAGUUGCACUUGACCUAGGUGCCCUUUCUGCUACAUGCAAAUGGCCUCUAAGAAGAACGAGGAACGUAUGUGUCCAGGUUGGCUUGAUUUCACCAGUUCACUCAGCUAUGGCCACGAUUUACUGACAUCAGCUCUGCAAUUGAGAGGUCCUGUCUCCAGGGGGAGGCUCGCUGGGCUUGCUCCUGACGAGGGGACCCCCAUUGAGGGUCAGUUCCCAGAGGAGAGUGGGGUGGGUCUGGAAACCCCCGAGGGGCAAGGUGGAGGAGCUCUCCUGUCGUAGCGGCUGGUCAGGGCCAGUUCUGCUCCCUGGCUCCACUGAGCUCGCCUGAGCCUGUGAGGUUGCCAGGGGUUCCCUGUGGCACGGCAGGCACUUCUGGAUGCAGAGGUGGAGGUUGAGGCCGUGACUCCAGGGGCAUGUUUGGUGGUGCUUGGGGCUGUUCCUGUGAACAGAGCAGAGUGGGAGGCAGGCAUCAUAGUUGCUGCAGAACAGUCCAUACUGUGGGGCUGGGGGGUUUCCUGCCACACCUGCCAUCUGCCCGGACCCCAUAGGGAAGGCCACACAGGCAAAUUCCUGAGAAGGGUCAGCCAGCUCACAAAGGUGGCCAUUCUAGAGAAAUCUCAGAGGAGAGGAAGUGCUUUGUCAGGAACUAGGCCUCAGGUCUUUCCCUGGAGGCCACUUCUUCCUACAUUGAUUUAGGAUGGGGGGGGUGGGGGGUGGAGGGGAGCAGGUUGACCUCCCAUCCAGCGCUGUAUCUGAGUGUAGUUCAUUUUAUAUCCAUAGCCCAAGCCAACUUGUAUCUUGGUGAUAUGGUUUGGCUGCGUCACGACACAAAUCUCACCUUGAAUUGUAAUAAUCCCCACGUGUCGUGGGAAGGACCCAGUGGGAGGUAAUUGAAUCAUGGGGGCGGGUCUUCCCAUGCUGUUCUCGUGAUAGUAAGUCUCAUGAGAUCUGAUGGUUUUAUAAAGGGGAGUUUCCCUGCACAUGCCCUUUUGCCUGUGUCAUGUAAGAUGUGGCUUUGCUCUUCCUUUGCCUUCUGCCAUGACUGUGAAGCCUCCCCCGCCAUGUGAAACUGUGAGUCCAUUAAACCUCUUUCCUUUAUAAAUUA